AGGACUCGCCGCUGCCCGCGCCCCGCCGCCGCUGCUGCCCCCAGCCCCGGCCCCAGGCGUCCCAGCCAUGGUCCGCCCAAUGCUCUUGCUCAGCCUCGGCCUCCUGGCUGGUCUGCUGCCGGCGCUGGCCGCCUGCCCCCAGAACUGCCACUGCCACAGCGACCUGCAGCACGUCAUCUGCGACAAGGUGGGGCUGCAGAAGAUCCCCAAGGUGUCAGAGAAGACCAAGCUGCUCAACCUACAGCGCAACAACUUCCCGGUGCUGGCUGCCAAUUCGUUCCGGGCCAUGCCGAACCUCGUGUCAUUGCACCUGCAGCACUGCCAGAUCCGCGAGGUGGCCGCCGGUGCCUUCCGCGGCCUCAAGCAACUUAUCUACUUGUACCUGUCCCAUAACGACAUCCGCGUGCUGCGCGCAGGUGCCUUCGACGACCUGACCGAGCUGACCUACCUCUACCUGGACCACAACAAGGUCACUGAGCUGCCCCGGGGGUUGCUCUCCCCGCUGGUCAACCUCUUCAUCUUGCAGCUCAACAACAACAAGAUCCGUGAGCUGCGCGCAGGCGCCUUCCAGGGAGCCAAGGACCUGCGCUGGCUCUACCUGUCGGAAAACGCGUUGAGCUCCCUGCAGCCCGGGGCCCUGGACGACGUGGAGAACCUCGCCAAAUUCCACGUGGACAGGAACCAGCUGUCCAGCUACCCCUCAGCUGCCCUGAGCAAGCUACGGGUGGUGGAGGAGCUGAAGCUGUCCCACAACCCCCUGAAAAGCAUCCCGGACAAUGCCUUCCAGUCCUUUGGCAGAUACCUGGAGACCCUCUGGCUGGACAACACCAACCUGGAGAAGUUCUCAGAUGGUGCCUUCCUGGGUGUAACCACGCUGAAACACGUCCAUUUGGAGAACAACCGCUUGAACCAGCUACCCUCCAACUUCCCCUUCGACAGCCUGGAGACCCUCGCCCUUACCAAUAACCCCUGGAAGUGUACCUGCCAGCUCCGGGGCCUUCGGCGGUGGCUGGAAGCCAAGGCCUCCCGCCCAGAUGCCACCUGUGCCUCACCUGCCAAGUUCAAGGGCCAGCACAUCCGUGACACGGACGCCUUCCGCAGCUGCAAGUUCCCCACCAAGAGGUCCAAGAAAGCUGGCCGCCAUUAAACAGGUGGGGGCCAGGUAAACAGGUCCCCUAUGUCCCUCUUUGGUGAUUCCAGCAAGUGAGCUGGUAUCUUCCAGGAUACCCCCUGGCCCUGGAGGGUCAGGCAGACCCUCCAUUUUUACAGAGAGAGGAGGGGACGACUGGGUCCCCUGUUGAAGGGAGGAAAAGGUCCUGCCCAGGACUUCCACCAUUUUCUUCAAGCAUCAUCUGUGUUGUUGGAGUACUGACAUCGAUCUUUGCCUCUUUGCAGGUUCUGACCCAGCCAGUCCUGGUGACUGGCCUCUGCCUUCCACCGGAGAGACUACUGACCUUCUCACCUCCACCCAUACCUUCUCCCCACAGCCUCUGCUGAUGCACAGAGCUGCCUACACCUAGACACGUCCUGGCAGGGGGCCUCGGGCACUCCACUACCAACCCAGCUCCACCCAGCAGUGUCCUGGGGAGAAGGAAGGCUGAGCCUCUCCCCAGCCUUCAUGCCUUCCCCACCCUCCAGCUCCUCUUGGAGAAGCUGUUGCUGAGACCCCCCCCCCAAGUCAAUCAGAACCACAACAGGUUGGUCAUCAGGAUGGCCACCCUCCCAGGAUCAUCCUUCCUCUGUUCCUCUUUCCCUGCCACGUGGAAACAAUCAUCAGAUCCUUGCCCCACCCCUUGCUUCCAGAAAGGGUUUUAAAGCCCAUGCCCCAACUCUGCCAGCCCCCACCUGCCAGGACGUUCUAGCAGGACAUCGGUGCUUUGCUGUCCAUCUUCCCAUGCUGCAAUUUCUUCCUGAGAUUUCUAUAAAUAUAAAUGUAUGUAUGUAUUAUA